GCACUUGGUUCGGGCCAGCCGCCUGAGGGGACGGGCUCACGUCUGCUCCUCACACUGCAGCUGCUGGGCCGUGGAGCUUCCCCAGGGAGCCAGGGGGACUUUUGCCGCAGCCAUGAAGGGGGCACGCUGGAGGAGGGUCCCCUGGGUGUCCCUGAGCUGCCUGUGUCUCUGCCUCCUUCCGCAUGUGGUCCCAGGAACCACAGAGGACACAUUAAUAACUGGAAGUAAAACUGCUGCCCCAGUCACCUCAACAGGCUCAACAACAGCGACACUAGAGGGACAAUCAACUGCAGCUUCUUCAAGGACCUCUAAUCAGGACAUAUCAGCUUCAUCUCAGAACCACCAGACUAAGAGCACGGAGACCACCAGCAAAGCUCAAACCGACACCCUCACGCAGAUGAUGACAUCAACUCUUUUUUCUUCCCCAAGUGUACACAAUGUGAUGGAGACAGCUCCUCCAGAUGAAAUGACCACAUCAUUUCCCUCCAGUGUCACCAACACACUCAUGAUGACAUCAAAGACUAUAACAAUGACAACCUCCACAGACUCCACUCUUGGAAACACAGAAGAGACAUCAACAGCAGGAACUGAAAGUUCUACCCCAGUGACCUCAGCAGUCUCAAUAACAGCUGGACAGGAAGGACAAUCACGAACAACUUCCUGGAGGACCUCUAUCCAAGACACAUCAGCUUCUUCUCAGAACCACUGGACUCGGAGCACGCAGACCACCAGGGAAUCUCAAACCAGCACCCUAACACACAGAACCACUUCAACUCCUUCUUUCUCUCCAAGUGUACACAAUGUGACAGGGACUGUUUCUCAGAAGACAUCUCCUUCAGGUGAAACAGCUACCUCAUCCCUCUGUAGUGUCACAAACACAUCCAUGAUGACAUCAGAGAAGAUAACAGUGACAACCUCCACAGGCUCCACUCUUGGAAACCCAGGGGAGACAUCAUCAGUACCUGUUACUGGAAGUCUUAUGCCAGUCACCUCAGCAGCCUUAGUAACAUUUGAUCCAGAAGGACAAUCACCAGCAACUUUCUCAAGGACUUCUACUCAGGACACAACAGCUUUUUCUAAGAACCACCAGACUCAGAGCGUGGAGACCACCAGAGUAUCUCAAAUCAACACCCUCAACACCCUCACACCGGUUACAACAUCAACUGUUUUAUCCUCACCAAGUGGAUUCAACCCAAGUGGAACAGUUUCUCAGGAGACAUUCCCUUCUGGUGAAACAACCACCUCAUCCCCUUCCAGUGUCAGCAAUACAUUCCUGGUAACAUCAAAGGUGUUCAGAAUGCCAACCUCCAGAGACUCUACUCUUGGAAACACAGAGGAGACAUCACUAUCUGUAAGUGGAACCAUUUCUGCAAUCACUUCCAAAGUUUCAACCAUAUGGUGGUCAGACACUCUGUCAACAGCACUCUCCCCCAGUUCUCUACCUCCAAAAAUAUCCACAGCUUUCCACACCCAGCAGAGUGAAGGUGCAGAGACCACAGGACGGCCUCAUGAGAGGAGCUCAUUCUCUCCAGGUGUGUCUCAAGAAAUAUUUACUCUACAUGAAACAACAACAUGGCCUUCCUCAUUCUCCAGCAAAGGCCACACAACUUGGUCACAAACAGAACUGCCCUCAACAUCAACAGGUGCUGCCACUAGGCUUGUCACAGGAAAUCCAUCUACAGGGACAGCUGGCACUAUUCCAAGGGUCCCCUCUAAGGUCUCAGCAAUAGGGGAACCAGGAGAGCCCACCACAUACUCCUCCCACAGCACAACUCUCCCAAAAACAACAGGGGCAGGCGCCCAGACACAAUGGACACAAGAAACGGGGACCACUGGAGAGGCUCUUCUCAGCAGCCCAAGCUACAGUGUGACUCAGAUGAUAAAAACGGCCACAUCCCCAUCUUCUUCACCUAUGCUGGAUAGACACACAUCCCAACAAAUUACAACGGCACCAUCAACAAAUCAUUCAACAAUACAUUCCACAAGCACCUCUCCUCAGGAAUCACCAGCUGUUUCCCAAAGGGGUCACACUCAAGCCCCGCAGACCACACAAGAAUCACAAACCACGAGGUCCGUCUCCCCCAUGACUGACACCAAGACAGUCACCACCCCAGGUUCUUCCUUCACAGCCAGUGGGCACUCGCCCUCAGAAAUUGUUCCUCAGGACGCACCCACCAUAAGUGCAGCAACAACCUUUGCCCCAGCUCCCACCGGGGAUGGUCACACAACCCAGGCCCCGACCACAGCACUGCAGGCAGCACCCAGCAGCCAUGAUGCCACCCUGGGGCCCUCAGGAGGCACGUCACUUUCCAAAACAGGUGCCCUUACUCUGGCCAACUCUGUAGUGUCAACACCAGGGGGCCCAGAAGGACAAUGGACAUCAGCCUCUGCCAGCACCUCACCUGACACAGCAGCAGCCAUGACCCAUACCCACCAGGCUGAGAGCACAGAGGCCUCUGGACAAACACAGACCAGCGAACCGGCCUCCUCAGGGUCACGAACCACCUCAGCGGGCACAGCUACCCCUUCCUCAUCCGGGGCGAGUGGCACAACACCUUCAGGAAGCGAAGGAAUAUCCACCUCAGGAGAGACGACAAGGUUUUCAUCAAACCCCUCCAGGGACAGUCACACAACCCAGUCAACAACCGAAUUGCUGUCCGCCUCAGCCAGUCAUGGUGCCAUCCCAGUAAGCACAGGAAUGGCGUCUUCGAUCGUCCCCGGCACCUUUCAUCCCACCCUCUCUGAGGCCUCCACUGCAGGGAGACCGACAGGACAGUCAAGCCCAACUUCUCCCAGUGCCUCUCCUCAGGAGACAGCCGCCAUUUCCCGGAUGGCCCAGACUCAGAGGACAAGAACCAGCAGAGGGUCUGACACUAUCAGCCUGGCGUCCCAGGCAACCGACACCUUCUCAACAGUCCCACCCACACCUCCAUCGAUCACAUCCACUGGGCUUACAUCUCCACAAACCGAGACCCACACUCUGUCACCUUCAGGGUCUGGUAAAACCUUCACCACGGCCCUCAUCAGCAACGCCACCCCUCUUCCUGUCACCUACGCUUCCUCGGCAUCCACAGGUCACACCACCCCUCUUCAUGUCACCGAUGCUUCCUCAGUAUCCACAGGUCACGCCACCCCUCUUCCUGUCACCAGCCCUUCCUCAGUAUCCACAGGUCACACCACCCCUCUUCCUGUCACCGACACUUCCUCAGAAUCCACAGGUCACGUCACCCCUCUUCCUGUCACCAGCUUUUCCUCAGCAUCCACAGGUGACAGCACCCCUCUUCCUGUCACUGACACUUCCUCAGCAUCCACAGGUCACGUCACCCCUCUUCCUGUCACCAGCCUUUCCUCAGCAUCCACAGGUGACACCACCCCUCUUCCUGUCACUGACACUUCCUCAGCAUCCACAGGUCACGCCACCUCUCUUCCUGUCACCGACACUUCCUCAGUAUCCACAGGUCACACCACCCCUCUUCCUGUCACCGACACUUCCUCAGCAUCCACAGGUCACGCCACCUCUCUUCCUGUCACCGACACUUCCUCAGUAUCCACAGGUCACACCACCCCUCUUCAUGUCACUGAUGCUUCCUCAGCAUCCACAGGUCAGGCCACCCCUCUUCCUGUCACCAGCCUUUCCUCAGUAUCCACAGGUGACACCACGCCUCUUCCUGUCACUAGCCCUUCCUCAGCAUCCACAGGUCACGCCACCCCUCUUCUUGUCACCGACACUUCCUCAGCAUCCACAGGACACGCCACCCCUCUUCCUGUCACCGACGCUUCCUCAGUGUCCACAGAUCACGCCACCUCUCUUCCUGUAACCAUCCCUUCCGCAGCAUCCACAGGUCACACCACCCCUCUUCCUGUCACCGACACUUCCUCAGCAUCCACAGGUCAGGCCACCUCUCUUCUUGUCACCGACACUUCCUCAGUAUCCACAGGUGACACCACGCCUCUUCCUGUCACUAGCACUUCCUCAGCAUCCACAGGUCACGUCACUCCUCUUCAUGUCACCAGCCCUUCCUCAGCAUCCACAGGUCACGCCACCCCUCUUCCUGUCACCAGCCUUUCCUCAGCAUCCACAGGUGACACCAUGCCUCUUCCUGUCACUAGCCCUUCCUCAGCAUCCACAGGUGACACCACCCCUCUUCCUGUCACCGACGCUUCCUCAGUAUCCACAGGUCACACCACCCCUCUUCAUGUCACUGAUGCUUCCUCAGCAUCCACAGGUCAGGCCACCCCUCUUCCUGUCACCAGCCUUUCCUCAGUAUCCACAGGUGACACCACGCCUCUUCCUGUCACUAGCCCUUCCUCAGCAUCCACAGGUCACGCCACCCCUCUUCUUGUCACCGACACUUCCUCAGCAUCCACAGGACACGCCACCCCUCUUCCUGUCACCGACGCUUCCUCAGUGUCCACAGAUCACGCCACCUCUCUUCCUGUAACCAUCCCUUCCGCAGCAUCCACAGGUCACACCACCCCUCUUCCUGUCACCGACACUUCCUCAGCAUCCACAGGUCAGGCCACCUCUCUUCUUGUCACCGACACUUCCUCAGUAUCCACAGGUGACACCACGCCUCUUCCUGUCACUAGCACUUCCUCAGCAUCCACAGGUCACGUCACUCCUCUUCAUGUCACCAGCCCUUCCUCAGCAUCCACAGGUCACGCCACCCCUCUUCCUGUCACCAGCCUUUCCUCAGCAUCCACAGGUGACACCAUGCCUCUUCCUGUCACUAGCCCUUCCUCAGCAUCCACAGGUGACACCACCCCUCUUCCUGUCACCGACGCUUCCUCAGUAUCCACAGGUCACACCACCCCUCUUCCUGUCACCAGCCCUUCCUCAGCAUCUACAGGUCACACCACCCCUCUUCCUGUCACCGACACUUCCUCAGCAUCCAAAGGUGACACCACCCCUCUUCCUGUCACCAGCCCUUCCUCAGCAUCUACAGGUCACACCACCCCUCUUCCUGUCACCGACACUUCCUCAGCAUCCACAGGUGACACCACCCCUCUUCCUGUCACCAAUGCUUCCUCAUUAUCCACAGGUCACGCCACCCCUCUUCAUGUCACCAGCCCUUCCUCAGCAUCCACAGGUCACGCCACCCCUCUUCCUGUCACCAGCACUUCCUCAGCAUCCACCGGUCACGCCACCCCUCUUCCUGUCACCGGCCUUUCCUCAGCUACCACAGAUGACACCACCCGUCUUCCUGUCACCGACGUUUCCUCGGCAUCCACAGGUCAGGCCACCCCUCUUCCUGUCACCAGCCUUUCCUCAGUAUCCACAGGUGACACCACGCCUCUUCCUGUCACUAGCCCUUCCUCAGCAUCCACAGGUCACGCCAGCCCUCUUCUUGUCACUGACGCUUCCUCAGCAUCCACAGGUCAGGCCACCCCUCUUCCUGUCACCGACACUUCCUCAGUAUCCACAGCUCACGCCACCCCACUUCCUGUCACCGGCCUUUCUUCAGCUUCCACAGAUGACACCACCCGUCUUCCUGUCACCGACGUUUCCUCGGCAUCCACAGGUCAGGCCAUCCCUCUUCCUGUCACCAGCCCUUCCUCAGCAUCCACAGGUGACACCACCCCUCUUCCUGUCACCGACGCUUCCUCAGCAUCCACAGGUGACACCACCUCUCUUCCUGUCACCAUCCCUUCCUCAGCAUCUUCAGGUCACACCACCUCUCUUCCUGUCACCGACGCUUCCUCAGUGUCCACAGGUCACGCCACCUCUCUUCUUGUCACCGACGCUUCCUCAGUAUCCACAGGUGACACCACCCCUCUUCCUGUCACCGACACUAACUCAGCAUCCACAGGUGACACCACCCCUCUUCAUGUCACCGACGCUUCCUCAGUAUCCACAGGUCACGCCACCUCUCUUCCUGUCACCAGCCUUUCCUCAGCAUCCACAGGUGACACCACGCCUCUUCCUGUCACUAGCCCUUCCUCAGCAUCCUCAGGUCACACCACCCCUCUUCCUGUCACCGACGCUUCCUCAGUACCCACAGGUCACGCCACCUCUCUUCCUGUCACCGACGCUUCCUCAGUGUCCACAGGUCACGCCACCCCUCUUCCUGUCACCGACGCUUCCUCAGUGUCCACAGGUCAUGCCACCCCUCUUCCGGUCACCGACACUUCCUCAGUAUCUACAGGACAGGCCACCCCUCUUCCUGUCACCAGCCUUUCCUCAGCAUCCACUGGUGACACCACGCCGCUUCCUGUCACCGAUACUUCCUCAGCAUCCACAGGUCAGGACACCCCUCUUCCUGUCACCAGCCUUUCCUCAGUAUCCACAGGUGACACCACGCCUCUUCCUGUCACUAACCCUUCCUCAGCAUCCACAGGUCACGCCACCCCUCUUCUUGUCACCGACGCUUCCUCAAUAUCCACAGGUCACGCCACCUCUCUUCUUGUCACCGACGCUUCCUCAGUAUCCACAGGUCACGCCACCGCUCUUCAUGACACCGAUGCUUCCUCAUUAUCCACAGGGGACACCACCCCUCUUCCUGUCACCAGCCCUUCCUCAACAUCCACAGGUGACACCACCCCUCUUCCUGUCACCGAAACUUCCUCAGUAUCCACAGGUCACGCCACCUCUCUUCCUGUCACCGACACUUCCUCAGCAUCCACAGGUCACGCCACCUCUCUUCCUGUCACCGACACUUCCUCAGCAUCCACAGGUCACGCCACCCCUCUUCCUGUCACCGACACUUCCUCAGCAUCCACAGGUCAGGCCACCCCUCUUCCUGUCACCAGCCCUUCCUCAGCAUCCACAGGUCACGCCAUCCCUCUUCUUGUCACCGACACUUCCUCAGCAUCCACAGGACAGGCCACCCCUCUUCCUGUCACCAGCCUUUCCUCAGCAUCCACAGGUGACACCACCCCUCUUCCUGUCACCGACGCUUCCUCAGUGUCCACAGGUCACGCCACCUCUCUUCCUGUCACCAGCCUUUCCUCAGUAUCCACAGGUGACACCACUCCUCUUCCUGUCACUAGCCCUUCCUCAGCAUCCACAGGUCACGCCACCCCUCUUCAUGUCACCGACGCUUCCUCAGCAUCCACAGGUCACGCCACCCCUCUUCCUGUCACCAGCCUUUCCUCAGCAUCCACAGGUGACACCACGCCUCUUCCUGUCACUAGCCCUUCCUCAGCAUCCACAGGUCACGCCACCCCUCUUCAUGUCACCGACGCUUCCUCAGUAUCCACAGGUGACACCACCCCUCUUCCUGUCACCAGCUCUUCCUCAGCAUCCUCAGGUCACACCACCCCUCUUCCUGUCACCGACGCUUCCUCAGCAUCCACAGGUGACACCACCCCUCUUCCUGUCACCGACACUUCCUCAGCAUCCACAGGUCACGCCACCCAUCUUCCUGUCACCGGCCUUUCCUCAGCUUCCACAGGUGACACCACCCGUCUUCCUGUCACCAACGUUUCCUCGGCAUCCACAGGUCAUGCCACCCCUCUUCCUGUCACCAGCACUUCCUCAGCAUCCACAGGUGACACCACCCCUCUUCCUGGCACCGACACUUCCUCAGUAUCCACAGGUCACACCACCCCUCUUCUUGUCACCGACGCUUCGUCAGUAUCCACAGGUGACACCACCCGUCUUCCUGUCACCAGCCCUUCCUCAGCAUCUACAGGUCACACCACCCCUCUACCUGUCACCGACACUCCCUCAGCAUCCACAGGUGACACCACCCCUCUUCCUGUCACCAAUGCUUCCUCAUUAUCCACACGUCACGCCACCUCUCUUCAUGUCACCAGCCCUUCCUCAGCAUCCACAGGUCACGCCACCUCUCUUCCUGUCACCGACACUUCCGCAGCAUCCACAGGUCACGCCACCCCUCUUCCUGUCACCAGCACUUCCUCAGCAUCCACAGGUGACACCACCCCUCUUCCUGUCACCGACACUUACUCAGCAUCCACAGGUCAGGCCACCCCUCUUCCUGUCACCAGCCUUUCCUCAGUAUCCACAGGUGACACCACGCCUCUUCCUGUCACUAGCCCUUCCUCAGCAUCCACAGGUCACGCCACUCCUCUUCUUGUCACCGACGCUUCCUCAGCAUCCACAGGUCAGGCCACCCCUCUUCCUGUCACCAGCCUUUCCUCAGUAUCCACAGGUGACACCACGCCUCUUCCUGUCACUAGCCCUUCCUCAGCAUCCACCGGUCAUGCCACCUCUCUUCCUGUCACCGACACUUCCUCAGCAUCCACAGGUGACACCACCUCUCUUCCUGUCACCGACACUUCCUCAGCAUACACAGGUGACACCACCUCUCUUCCUGUCACCGACACUUCCUCAUCAUCCACAGGUGACACCACCCCUCUUCUUGUCACCGAGACUUCCUCAGUAUCCACAGGUGACACCACCCCUCUUCCUGUCACCGACACUUCCUCAGCAUCCACAGGUCACGCCACCCCUCUUCCUGUCACCAACACUUCCUCAGUAUCCACAGGUCACGCCACCCCUCUUCAUGUCACCAGCCCUUCCUCAGCAUCCACAGGUCACACCACCCCUCUUCCUGUCACCGACGCUUCGUCAGUGUCCACAGGUCACGCCACCUCUCUUCCUGUCACCGACGCUUCCUCAGUGUUCACAGGUCAUGCCACCUCUCUUCCUGUCACCAUCCCUUCCUCAGCAUCCUCAGGUCACACCACCCCUCUUCCUGUCACCGACGCUUCCUCAGUGUCCACAGGUCACGCCACCUCUCUUCCUGUCACCGACGCUUCCUCAGUGUCCACAGGUCAUGCCACCCCUCUUCCUGUCACCGACGCUUCCUCAGUGUCCACAGGUCACGCUACCCCUCUUCCUCUCACCAGCCUUUCCUCAGUAUCCACAGGUGACACCACGCCUCUUCCUGUCACCGACACUUCCUCAGCAUCCACAGGUCAGGCCACCCCUCUUCCUGUCACCAGCCUUUCCUCAGUAUCCACAGGUGACACCACCCCUCUUCCUGUCACCGACACUUCCUCAGCAUCCACAGGUCACGCCACCUCUCUUCCUGUCACCGACACUUCCUCAGCAUCCACAGGUCACGCCACCCCUCUUCCUGACACCGACACUUCCUCAGCAUCCACAGGUCACGCCACCCUUCUUCCUGUCACCGACACUUCCUCAGCAUCCAUAGGUCACGCCACCUCUCUUCCUGUCACCGACACUUCCUCAAUAUCCACAGGUCACGCCACCCCUCUUCAUGUCACCAGCCCUUCCUCAGCAUCCACCGGUCACGCCACCCCGCUUCCUGUCACCGACACUUCCUCAGCAUCCACAGGUCACGCCAACCCUCUUCAUGUCACCAGCCCUUCCUCAGCAUCCACCGGUCACGCCACCCCGCUUCCUGUCACCGACACUUCCUCAGCAUCCACAGGUCACGCCACCCCUCUUCCUGUCACCAGCCUUUCCUCAGUAUCCACAGGUGACACCACGCCUCUUCCUGUCACUAGCCCUUCCUCAGCAUCCACAGGUCACACCACCCCUCUUCCUGUCACCGACACUUCCUCAGCAUCCACAGGUCAGGCCACCGCUCUUCCUGUCACCAGCACUUCCUCAGCAUCCACAGGUGACACCACCCCUCUUCCUGUCACCGACACUUCCUCAGCAUCCACAGGUCAGGCCACCCCUCUUCCUGUCACCAGCCUUUCCUCAGUAUCCACAGGUGACACCACGCCUCUUCCUGUCACUAGCCCUUCCUCAGCAUCCACAGGUCACGCCACUCCUCUUCUUGUCACCGACGCUUCCUCAGCAUCCACAGGUCAGGCCACCCCUCUUCCUGUCACCAGCCUUUCCUCAGUAUCCACAGGUGACACCACGCCUCUUCCUGUCACUAGCCCUUCCUCAGCAUCCACCGGUCAUGCCACCUCUCUUCCUGUCACCGACACUUCCUCAGCAUCCACAGGUGACACCACCUCUCUUCCUGUCACCGACACUUCCUCAGCAUACACAGGUGACACCACCUCUCUUCCUGUCACCGACACUUCCUCAUCAUCCACAGGUGACACCACCCCUCUUCUUGUCACCGAGACUUCCUCAGUAUCCACAGGUCACGCCACUCCUCUUCUUGUCACCGACGCUUCCUCAGCAUCCACAGGUCACGCCACCCCUCUUCAUGUCACCAGCCCUUCCUCAGCAUCCACAGGUGACACCACCCCUGUGCCUGUCACCGACACUUCCUCAGUAUCCACAGGUCACGCCACCCCUCUUCCUGUCACCGGCCUUUCCUCAGCUUCCACAGGUGACACCACCCGUCUUCCUGUCACCGACAUUUCCUCGGCAUCCACAGGUCAGGCCACCCCUCUUCCUGUCACCAACACUUCCUCAGUAUCCACAGGUGACACCAUGCCUCUUCCUGUCACUAGCCCUUCCUCAGCAUCCACAGGUCACGCCACCCCUCUUCCUGUCACCAGCACUUCCUCAGCAUCCACCGGUCACGCCACCCCUGUUCCUGUCACCAGCACUUCCUCAGCAUCUACAGGUCACACCACCCCUCUUCCUGUCACCGACACUUCCUCAGCAUCCACAGGUGACACCACCCCUCUUCCUGUCACCAGCCCUUCCUCAGCAUCUACAGGUCACACCACCCCUCUUCAUGUCACCAUCCCUUCCUCAGCAUCCACAGGUGACACCAGCACUCUUCCUGUCACCGGCGCUUCCUCAGCAUCCACCGGUCACGCCACCCCUCUUCCUGUCACCGACACUUCCUCAGUAUCCACCGGUCACGCCACGCCUCUUCCUGUCACCAGCCUUUCCUCAGUAUCCACAGGUGACACCACCCCUCUUCCUGUCACCGACGCUUCCUCGGCAUCCACAGGUCAGGCCACCCCUCUUCCUGUCACCAGCCUUUCCUCAGUAUCCACAGGUGACACCACCCCUCUUCUUGUCACCGACGCUUCCUCAGUAUCCACAGGUCACGCCACCCCUCUUCCUGUCACCGACACUUCCUCAGCAUCCACAGGUGACACCACCCGUCUUCCUGUCACGGACACUUCCUCAGCAUCCACAGGUCAGGCCACCCCUCUUCCUGUCACCAGCCUUUCCUCAGUAUCCACAGGUGACACCACCCCUCUUCUUGUCACCGACGCUUCCUCAGUAUCCACAGGUCACGCCACCCCUCUUCCUGUCACCGACACUUCCUCAGCAUCCACAGGUGACACCACCCGUCUUCCUGUCACGGACACUUCCUCAGCAUCCACAGGUCAGGCCACCCCUCUUCCUGUCACCAUCCCUUCCUCAUCAUCCUCAGGUCACACCACCCCUCUUCCUGUCACCAGCACUUCCUCAGUAUCUACAGGUCACGUCACCCCUCUUCAUGUCACCAGCCCUUCCUCAGCAUCCACAGGUCACGUCACCCCUCUUCCUGUCACCAGCACUUCCUCAGCAUCCACAGGUCACGCCACCCCUCUUCUUGUCACCGACGCUUCCUCAGUGUCCACAGGUCACGCCACGCCUCUUCCUGUCACCGACGCUUCCUCAGCAUCCACAGGUGACACCACCCCUCUUCCUGUCACCGACACUUCCUCAGCAUCCACAGGUCAGGCCACCCCUCUUCCUGUCACCAGCCUUUCCUCAGUAUCCACAGGUGACACCACCCCUCUUCCUGUCACCGACGCUUCCUCAGCAUCCACAGGUCACGCCACCCCUCUUCCUGUCACCAUCCCUUCCUCAGUAUCCACAGGUGACACCAUGCCUCUUCCUGUCACUAGCCCUUCCUCAGCAUCCACAGGUCACGCCACCCCUCUUCCUGUUACCGGCCUUUCCUCAGCUUCCACAGGUGACACCACCCCUCUUCCUGUCACCGACACUUCCUCAGCAUCCACACGUCACGCCACCCCUCUUCCUGUCACCGACACUUCCUCAGCUUCCACAGAUGACACCACCCGUCUUCCUGUCACCGACGUUUCCUCGGCAUCCACAGGACAUGCCACCCCUCUUCCUGUCACCAGCACUUCCUCAGCAUCCACAGGUGACACCACCCCUCUUCCUGUCACCGACACUUCCUCAGUAUCCACAGGUCACGCCACCUCUCUUCCUGUCACCAGCCGUUCCUCAGCAUCCACAGGUCACGCCACCCCCCUUCCUGUCACCGACACUUCCUCAGUAUCCACAGGUCACGCCACCCCUCUUCCUGUCACCAGCACUUCCUCAGUAUCUACAGGUCACGCCACCCCUCUUCCUGUCACCAGCCCUUCCUCAGCAUCCACAGGUCACGCCACCCCUGUUCCUGUCACCAGCACUUCCUCAGCAUCCACAGGUGACACCACCCCUCUUCCUGUCACCAAUGCUUCCUCAUUAUCCACAGGUCACGCCACCCCUCUUCAUGUCACCAGCCCUUCCUCAGCAUCCAGAGGUGACACCAGCACUCUUCCUGUCACCGAUGCUUCCUCAGCAUCCACCGGUCACGCCACCCCUCUUCCUCUCACCAGCCUUUCCUCAGUAUCCACAGGUGACACCACGCCUCUUCCUGUCACCGACACUUCCUCUGCAUCCACAGGUCAGGCCACCCCUCUUCCUGUCACCAGCCUUUCCUCAGUAUCCACAGGUGACACCACGCCUCUUCCUGUCACCAUCCCUUCCUCAGCAUCCUCAGGUCACACCACCUCUCUUCCUGUCACCGACGCUUCCUCAGUGUCCACAGGUCACGGCACCCCUCUUCCUGUCACCAGCACUUCCUCAGCAUCCACAGGUGACACCACCCCUCUUCCUGUCACCGACACUUCCUCAGCAUCCACAGGUCACGCCACCCCUCUUCCUGUCACCGACACUUCCUCAGCAUCCACAGGUCACGCCACCCCUCUUCCUGUCACCAGCCUUUCCUCAGUAUCCACAGGUCACGCCACCCCUCUUGCUGUCAGCAGUGCUACCUCAGCUUCCACAGUAUCCUCGGACUCCCCUCUGAAGAUGGAAACACCAGGAAUGACAACACCGUCACUGAAGACAGACGGUGGGAGACGCACAGCCACAUCACCACCCCCCACAACCUCCCAGACCAUCAUUUCCACCAUUCCCAGCACUGCCAUGCACACCCGCUCCACAGCUGCCCCCAUCCCCAUCCUGCCUGAGAGAGGAGUUUCCCUCUUCCCCUAUGGGGCAGGCGCCGGGGACCUGGAGUUCGUCAGGAGGACCGUGGACUUCACCUCCCCACUCUUCAAGCCGGCGACUGGCUUCCCCCUUGGCUCCUCUCUCCGUGAUUCCCUCUACUUCACAGACAAUGGCCAGAUCAUCUUCCCAGAGUCAGACUACCAGAUUUUCUCCUACCCCAACCCACUCCCAACAGGCUUCACAGGCCGGGACCCUGUGGCCCUGGUGGCUCCGUUCUGGGACGAUGCUGACUUCUCCACUGGUCGGGGGACCACAUUUUAUCAGGAAUACGAGACGUUCUAUGGUGAACACAGCCUGCUAGUCCAGCAGGCCGAGUCUUGGAUUAGAAAGAUGACAAACAACGGGGGCUACAAGGCCAGGUGGGCCCUAAAGGUCACGUGGGUCAAUGCCCACGCCUAUCCUGCCCAGUGGACCCUCGGGAGCAACACCUACCAAGCCAUCCUCUCCACGGACGGGAGCAGGUCCUAUGCCCUGUUUCUCUACCAGAGCGGUGGGAUGCAGUGGGACGUGGCCCAGCGCUCAGGCAACCCGGUGCUCAUGGGCUUCUCUAGUGGAGAUGGCUAUUUCGAAAACAGCCCACUGAUGUCCCAGCCAGUGUGGGAGAGGUAUCGCCCUGAUAGAUUCCUGAAUUCCAACUCAGGCCUCCAAGGGCUGCAGUUCUACAGGCUACACCGGGAAGAAAGGCCCAACUACCGUCUCGAGUGCCUGCAGUGGCUGAAGAGCCAGCCUCGGUGGCCCAGCUGGGGCUGGAACCAGGUCUCCUGCCCUUGUUCCUGGCAGCAGGGACGACGGGACUUACGAUUCCAACCCGUCAGCAUAGGUCGCUGGGGCCUCGGCAGUAGGCAGCUGUGCAGCUUCACCUCUUGGCGAGGAGGCGUGUGCUGCAGCUACGGGCCCUGGGGAGAGUUUCGUGAAGGCUGGCACGUGCAGCGUCCUUGGCAGUUGGCCCAGGAACUGGAGCCACAGAGCUGGUGCUGCCGCUGGAAUGACAAGCCCUACCUCUGUGCCCUGUACCAGCAGAGGCGGCCCCACGUGGGCUGUGCUACAUACAGGCCCCCACAGCCCGCCUGGAUGUUCGGGGACCCCCACAUCACCACCUUGGAUGGUGUCAGUUACACCUUCAAUGGGCUGGGGGACUUCCUGCUGGUCGGGGCCCAAGACGGGAACUCCUCCUUCCUGCUUCAGGGCCGCACCGCCCAGACUGGCUCAGCCCAGGCCACCAACUUCAUCGCCUUUGCGGCUCAGUACCGCUCCAGCAGCCUGGGCCCCGUCACGGUCCAAUGGCUCCUUGAGCCUCACGACGCAAUCCGUGUCCUGCUGGAUAACCAGACUGUGACAUUUCAGCCUGACCAUGAAGACGGCGGAGGCCAGGAGACGUUCAACGCCACCGGAGUCCUCCUGAGCCGCAACGGCUCUGAGGUCUCGGCCAGCUUCGACGGCUGGGCCACCGUCUCGGUGAUCGCGCUCUCCAACAUCCUCCACGCCUCCGCCAGCCUCCCGCCCGAGUACCAGAACCGCACGGAGGGGCUCCUGGGGGUCUGGAAUAACAAUCCAGAGGACGACUUCAGGAUGCCCAAUGGCUCCACCAUUCCCCCAGGGAGCCCUGAGGAGAUGCUUUUCCACUUUGGAAUGACCUGGCAGAUCAACGGGACAGGCCUCCUUGGCAAGAGGAAUGACCAGCUGCCUUCCAACUUCACCCCUGUUUUCUACUCACAACUGCAAAAAAACAGCUCCUGGGCUGAACAUUUGAUCUCCAACUGUGACGGAGAUAGCUCAUGCAUCUAUGACACCCUGGCCCUGCGCAACGCAAGCAUCGGACUUCACACGAGGGAAGUCAGUAAAAACUACGAGCAGGCGAACGCCACCCUCAAUCAGUACCCGCCCUCCAUCAAUGGUGGUCGUGUGAUUGAAGCCUACAAGGGGCAGACCACGCUGAUUCAGUACACCAGCAAUGCUGAGGAUGCCAACUUCACGCUCAGAGACAGCUGCACCGACUUGGAGCUCUUUGAGAAUGGGACGUUGCUGUGGACACCCAAGUCGCUGGAGCCAUUCACUCUGGAGAUUCUAGCAAGAAGUGCCAAGAUUGGCUUGGCAUCUGCACUCCAGCCCAGGACUGUGGUCUGCCAUUGCAAUGCAGAGAGCCAGUGUUUGUACAAUCAGACCAGCAGGGUGGGCAACUCCUCCCUGGAGGUGGCUGGCUGCAAGUGUGACGGGGGCACCUUCGGCCGCUACUGCGAGGGCUCCGAGGAUGCCUGUGAGGAGCCGUGCUUCCCGAGUGUCCACUGCGUUCCUGGGAAGGGCUGCGAGGCCUGCCCUCCAAACCUGACUGGGGAUGGGCGGCACUGUGCGGCUCUGGGGAGCUCUUUCCUGUGUCAGAACCAGUCCUGCCCUGUGAAUUACUGCUACAAUCAAGGCCACUGCUACAUCUCCCAGACUCUGGGCUGUCAGCCCAUGUGCACCUGCCCCCCAGCCUUCACUGACAGCCGCUGCUUCCUGGCUGGGAACAACUUCAGUCCAACUGUCAACCUAGAACUUCCCUUAAGAGUCAUCCAGCUCUUGCUCAGUGAAGAGGAAAAUGCCUCCAUGGCAGAAGUCAACGCCUCGGUGGCAUACAGACUGGGGACCCUGGACAUGCGGGCCUUUCUCCGCAACAGCCAAGUGGAACGAAUCGAUUCUGCAGCACCGGCCUCGGGAAGCCCCAUCCAACACUGGAUGGUCAUCUCGGAGUUCCAGUACCGCCCUCGGGGCCCGGUCAUUGACUUCCUGAACAACCAGCUGCUGGCCGCGGUGGUGGAGGCGUUCUUAUACCACGUUCCACGGAGGAGUGAGGAGCCCAGGAACGACGUGGUCUUCCAGCCCAUCUCCGGGGAAGACGUGCGCGAUGUGACAGCCCUGAACGUGAGCACGCUGAAGGCUUACUUCAGAUGCGAUGGCUACAAGGGCUACGACCUGGUCUACAGCCCCCAGAGCGGCUUCACCUGCGUGUCCCCGUGCAGUAGGGGCUACUGUGACCAUGGAGGCCAGUGCCAGCACCUGCCCAGUGGGCCCCGCUGCAGCUGUGUGUCCUUCUCCAUCUACACGGCCUGGGGCGAGCACUGUGAGCACCUGAGCAUGAAACUCGACGCGUUCUUCGGCAUCUUCUUUGGGGCCCUGGGCGGCCUCUUGCUGCUGGGGGUCGGGACGUUCGUGGUCCUGCGCUUCUGGGGUUGCUCCGGGGCCAGGUUCUCCUAUUUCCUGAACUCAGCUGAGGCCUUGCCUUGAAGGGGCAGCUGUGGCCUAGGCUACCUCAAGACUCACCUCAUCCUUACCGCACAUUUAAGGCGCCAUUGCUUUUGGGAGACUGGAAAAGGGAAGGUGACUGAAGGCUGUCAGGAUUCUUCAAGGAGAAUGAAUACUGGGAAUCAAGACAAGACUAUACCUUAUCCAUAGGCGCAGGUGCACAGGGGGAGGCCAUAAAGAUCAAACAUGCAUGGAUGGGUCCUCACGCAGACACACCCACAGAAGGACACUAGCCUGUGCACGCGCGCGUGCACACACACACACACACACACGAGUUCAUAAUGUGGUGAUGGCCCUAAGUUAAGCAAAAUGCUUCUGCACACAAAACUCUCUGGUUUACUUCAAAUUAACUCUAUUUAAAUAAAGUCUCUCUGACUUUUUGUGUCU